GUUGACCGCGUGCCGGGUGUCAUGGCGGCCUGCAGGUACUGCUGCUCGUGCCUCCGGCUCCGGCCCCUGAGCGAUGGUCCUUUCCUUCUGCCACGGCGGGAUCGGGCACUCACCCAGUUGCAAGUGCGAGCACUAUGGAGUAGCGCAGGGUCUCGAGCUGUGGCCGUGGACUUAGGCAACAGGAAAUUAGAAAUAUCUUCUGGAAAGCUGGCCAGAUUUGCAGAUGGCUCUGCUGUAGUACAGUCAGGUGACACUGCAGUAAUGGUCACAGCGGUCAGUAAAACAAAACCUUCCCCUUCCCAGUUUAUGCCUUUGGUGGUUGACUACAGACAAAAAGCUGCUGCAGCAGGUAGAAUUCCCACAAACUAUCUGAGAAGAGAGAUUGGUACUUCUGAUAAAGAAAUUCUAACAAGUCGAAUAAUAGAUCGUUCAAUUAGACCGCUCUUUCCAGCUGGCUACUUCUAUGAUACACAGGUUCUGUGUAAUCUGUUAGCAGUAGAUGGUGUAAAUGAGCCUGAUGUCCUAGCAAUUAAUGGCGCUUCCGUAGCCCUCUCAUUAUCAGAUAUUCCUUGGAAUGGACCUGUUGGGGCAGUACGAAUAGGAAUAAUUGAUGGAGAAUAUGUUGUUAACCCAACAAGAAAAGAAAUGUCUUCUAGUACUUUAAAUUUAGUGGUUGCUGGAGCACCUAAAAGUCAGAUUGUCAUGUUGGAAGCCUCUGCAGAGAACAUUUUACAGCAGGACUUUUGCCAUGCUAUCAAAGUGGGAGUGAAAUAUACCCAACAAAUAAUUCAGGGCAUUCAGCAGUUGGUAAAAGAAACUGGUGUUACCAAGAGGACACCUCAGAAGUUAUUUACCCCUUCGCCAGAGAUUGUGAAAUAUACUCAUAAACUUGCUAUGGAGAGACUCUAUGCAGUUUUUACAGAUUACGAGCAUGACAAAGUUUCCAGAGAUGAAGCUGUUAACAAAAUAAGAUUAGAUACGGAGGAACAACUAAAAGAAAAAUUUCCAGAAGCCGAUCCAUAUGAAAUAAUAGAAUCCUUCAAUGUUGUUGCAAAGGAAGUUUUUAGAAGUAUUGUUUUGAAUGAAUACAAAAGGUGCGAUGGUCGGGAUUUGACUUCACUUAGGAAUGUAAGUUGUGAGGUAGAUAUGUUUAAAACCCUUCAUGGAUCAGCAUUAUUUCAAAGAGGACAAACACAGGUGCUUUGUACCGUUACAUUUGAUUCAUUAGAAUCUGGUAUUAAGUCAGAUCAAGUUAUAACAGCUAUAAAUGGGAUAAAAGAUAAAAAUUUCAUGCUGCACUACGAGUUUCCUCCUUAUGCAACUAAUGAAAUUGGCAAAGUCACUGGUUUAAAUAGAAGAGAACUUGGGCAUGGUGCUCUUGCUGAGAAAGCUUUGUAUCCUGUUAUUCCCCGAGAUUUUCCUUUCACCAUAAGAGUUACAUCUGAAGUCCUAGAGUCAAAUGGGUCAUCUUCUAUGGCAUCUGCAUGUGGCGGAAGUUUAGCAUUAAUGGAUUCAGGGGUUCCAAUUUCAUCUGCUGUUGCAGGCGUAGCAAUAGGAUUGGUCACCAAAACCGAUCCUGAGAAGGGUGAAAUAGAAGAUUAUCGUUUGCUGACAGAUAUUUUGGGAAUUGAAGAUUACAAUGGUGACAUGGACUUCAAAAUAGCUGGCACUAAUAAAGGAAUAACUGCAUUACAGGCUGAUAUUAAAUUACCUGGAAUACCAAUAAAAAUUGUGAUGGAGGCUAUUCAACAAGCUUCAGUGGCAAAAAAGGAGAUAUUACAGAUCAUGAACAAAACUAUUUCAAAACCUCGAGCAUCUAGAAAAGAAAAUGGACCUGUUGUAGAAACUGUUCAGGUUCCAUUAUCAAAACGAGCAAAAUUUGUUGGACCUGGUGGCUAUAACUUAAAAAAACUUCAGGCUGAAACAGGUGUAACUAUUAGUCAGGUGGAUGAAGAAACGUUUUCUGUAUUUGCACCAACACCCAGUGCUAUGCAUGAGGCAAGAGACUUCAUUACUGAAAUCUGCAAGGAUGAUCAGGAGCAGCAAUUAGAAUUUGGAGCAGUAUAUACCGCCACAAUAACUGAAAUCAGAGAUACUGGUGUAAUGGUAAAAUUAUAUCCAAAUAUGACUGCGGUACUGCUUCAUAACACACAACUUGAUCAACGAAAGAUUAAACAUCCUACUGCCCUAGGAUUAGAAGUUGGCCAAGAAAUUCAGGUGAAAUACUUUGGACGUGACCCAGCCGAUGGAAGAAUGAGGCUUUCUCGAAAAGUGCUUCAGUCGCCAGCUACAACCGUGGUCAGAACUUUGAAUGACAGAAGUAGUAUUGUAAUGGGAGAACCUAUUUCACAGUCAUCAUCUAAUUCUCAGUGAUUUUUUUUUUUAAAGAGAAUUCUAGAAUUCUAUUUUGUCUAGGGUGAUGUGCUGUAGAGCAACAUUUUAGUAGUAUCUUCCAUUGUGUAGAUUUCUAUAUAAUAUAAAUACAUUUUAAUUAUUUGUACUAAAAUGCUCAUUUACAUGUGCCAUUUUUUUAAUUCGAGUAACCCAUAUUUGUUUAAUUGUAUUUACAUUAUAAAUCAAGAAAUAUUUAUUAUUAAAAGUAAGUCAUUUAUACAUCUUAGAAAAAAUUACAUAGUUUUGUUUUUACAAUUCUGAAAUAUAUGAAAAACUUAGAUAGAAUAUGUCAUAUGUUAUUAUAACAGAUCUCUUCCUACAUCUUAUUUUUCUUCUUUGUAUACAGUAGUGACAGUUUACCUUCAGUCAUCCUACAGGUCACCUCUGUGCCCAACAACUUUACUUGCCUACAACGGUUCACAAACUGGAACAGGCCAUAUUCAAAGCCAGUGCCUAUUUCUUCAGAACUGUUAACAGAUAUAGUGAGUUGAGGGAGCUAAUCUGAUACACUUUUGAUAAUAUAAUGCCUUUCAAAUUAGUUACCAAAUCAUAAACAGAGUGGAAUAAAUAUAAAUGAGAUUCUAACUAGGAUGAAUGUGGUAGUAAUGAUGUAUAUUUUUCAAAUUUACCUAAACAGAAAGAUUAUUGGCUAAGGCAGGCGGAUCAUGAGAUCAGGAGAUCGAGACCAUCCUGGCUAACACGGUGAAACCCCGUCUCUACUAAAAGUGCAAAAAUUAGCCGGGCGUGGUGGCGCAUGCCUGUAAUCCUAGCUACUCAGGAGGCUGAGGCAGAAGAAUCACUUCAACCCAGGAGGUGGAGGUUGUAGUGAGCCGAGAUUGCGCCAUUGCACUCCAGCUCAGGCAACAAGAGCAAAACUCCGUCUCAAAAAAAAAAAAAAAAUUGUUUACUUAUCAAAUUGAACUAGGUCAAUUUGAAUAUGUGUAUUGCUCUAAUGUAUGGAAGUUCUUAGUAUAAGAGCUGAAGGAUCAUGACUUUCGGUUAAUAGAUGUUUGAAAUAGAUGUUUAGAGGUUACUGAUACACAUGUCAAGUUGUUCAUUCCCAUCAUUUAAAAUAUCACCUUAUAAUUCCACAGAAAAGUAAAUGGUAUGUGGACGUCAUAAUUUAGAAUGUGUAAUCUUUUUUAAAAUCUUAUAAAAAUACACUGGACUCAGUGGUACGUGCCUGUAGUCCCAGCUACUUGGAAGGCUGAAGUGGGAAGGUCACUAGAGCCCAGAAGUUCGACACUGUAGUGUGCAACAAUCAUACCUGUGAAUAGCUACUGUACUCCAGCCUGGGCAACAUAGCAGGACUCUUAUCUCUAAAAAAAAUUUUAAAUCUUAUAAAAAUGUAGGUAUAUCUGGCCAGGCAUGGUGGCUCACACCUGUAAUCCCAACACUUUGGGAGGUCAAGGCGGGUAGAUCACCUGAGGUCAGGAGUUCGAGACCAGCCUGGCCAACAUGGUGAAACCCCAUCUCUACUAAAAAUACAAAAAUUAGCUGGGUGUGGUGGCGGGCGCCUGUAAUCCCAGCUACUCAGGAGGCUGAGGCAGGAGAAUCUCUUGAACCUGGGAGGCAGAGGUGGCAGUGAGCUGAGAUCGCACCACUGCACUCCAGCCUGGGCAAAAAGAGUAAAACUCCAUCUCAAAAAAAAAAAUGGUGGGCACAGAAGCUCAUGCCUGUAAUUCCAGCACUUUGGGAGGCCGAGGCGGGUGGAUUACAUGAGGUCAGGAAUUCAAGACCAGCCUGGCCAACACGGUAAAACCCCAUCUCUACUAAAAAUACAAAAAUUAGCUGGGCAUGGUGGCAGGCACCUGUAAUCCUAGCUACUCGGGAGGCUGAGGCAGGAGAAUCACUUGAGCCUGGGAAAUGGAGGUUGCAGUGAGCCGAGAUUGCGCCAUUGCACUCCAGCCUGGGCGACAGAGCAAGACUCCGUCUCCAGAAAAAAAAAAAAAAAAGGUAAAUUCAUGACUCAGGGUUAACUAGUUCAUAAAAUAUUACAAAUUUAUCUGGCUAAACCAAAGAUUUUUAAGUCAAUAAACAUUGAUUAUAUAUCUAUUGUGUGUAAAAUAGCAUGUUAGGCAAUGUUGAUAUACUUCUGAAAUAUUAAAGAUUAAUUGAAAAUGAAAGAUUAAAUUUAUUUGCUUUCUACACUUGA